GCCUUCCUGCUUUGUCCGGUGCACUGAGCACAGACGCUGCUCCUGUUCACCCUCGAGCGCCUAACUAAUAAGUCCUAAGCUCAAAUCACAGAAGUCCAGGGUGCUGCCAUUUCUUUUUGAAAAACAUCCCAGAGGAAAGAAGCUCCGCGGAGAGUUCCUGAAAUGCAGAGAGCCAGAGAAGCCGAAAUGAUGAAAAGUCAGGUACUGUUUCCCUUCCUGCUGUCUUUGUUCUGCGGGGCCAUCUCCCAGCAGAUCCGAUACACGAUUCCAGAGGAGCUAGCCAACGGCUCACGGGUGGGGAAACUUGCCAAGGAUCUGGGGCUCAGUGUCCGGGAGUUGCCAACUCGAAAACUGCGGGUUAGUGCAGAGGAUUAUUUCAACGUUAGUUUGGAGAGCGGGGAUUUGUUAGUGAACGGUAGGAUAGAUCGAGAGAAGAUUUGCGGAAGGAAACUUGAGUGUGCACUAGAAUUCGAAACGGUCGCUGAAAACCCAAUGAAUGUUUUCCACGUGGUUGUUGUAAUCCAAGAUAUUAAUGACAAUGCACCACGUUUCGUUGCAAAAGGCAUUGACUUAGAAAUUUGUGAGUCAGCCUUACCCGGGGUAAAAUUCUCUCUGGAUUCUGCUCAAGAUGCAGAUGUGGAAGGCAAUUCACUGAAGUUAUACACCAUCAACCCCAAUCAAUACUUCUCUCUGUCAACGAAGGAAAGUCCUGAUGGAAGUAAAUAUCCGGUAUUACUGCUGGAAAAACCUCUAGACAGGGAACAUCAGAGCUCUCAUCGCUUAAUCCUGACUGCCAUGGAUGGCGGGGACCCGCCUCUAAGCGGCACCACCCAUAUCUGGAUCCGAGUUACGGAUGCCAAUGAUAAUGCUCCCGUGUUUAGCCAGGAGGUAUACAGGGUUAGCCUCCAAGAAAACGUACCGUGGGGAACCUCCGUGCUGCGGGUGAUGGCCACAGACCAGGAUGAGGGCAUUAAUGCAGAGAUCACCUAUGCCUUCCUCAAUUCCCCAAUAAGUACCAGCCUCUUCAAUCUCAAUCCAAAUACUGGCGACAUCACAACCAAUGGCACAUUGGAUUUUGAAGAGACAAGUAGAUAUGUGUUGAGUGUGGAAGCUAAGGAUGGAGGAGUACACACAGCUCACUGUAAUGUUCAAAUAGAAAUUGUUGACGAGAAUGACAAUGCCCCAGAGGUGACAUUCAUGUCCUUCUCUAACCAGAUUCCAGAGGAUUCAGACCUUGGAACUGUAAUAGCCCUCAUAAAAGUGCGAGACAAGGAUUCUGGGCAAAAUGGCAUGGUGACAUGCUAUACUCAGGAAGAAGUUCCUUUCAAAUUAGAAUCCACCUCGAAGAAUUAUUACAAGCUGGUGAUUGCUGGAGCCCUAAACCGGGAGCAGACAGCAGACUACAACGUCACAAUCAUAGCCACCGACAAGGGCAAACCAGCCCUUUCCUCCAGGACAAGCAUCACCCUGCACAUCUCCGACAUCAACGACAAUGCACCUGUUUUCCAUCAGGCCUCCUAUGUGGUCCACGUGUCUGAGAACAACCCACCUGGCGCCUCCAUUGCACAAGUAAGCGCCUCCGACCCGGAUUUGGGACCCAACGGCAGAGUCUCCUACUCUAUUCUGGCCAGUGACCUGGAGCCGCGGGAGCUGUUGUCCUACGUGUCCGUGAGCCCGCAGAGCGGGGUGGUGUUCGCGCAGCGCGCCUUCGACCACGAGCAGCUGCGCGCCUUCGAGCUCACACUGCAGGCCAGGGACCAGGGCUCCCCCGCGCUCAGCGCCAACGUGAGCCUGCGCGUGUUGGUGGGCGACCUCAAUGACAAUGCGCCACGGGUGCUGUACCCCGCGCUGGGGCCUGAUGGCUCCGCCCUCUUCGAUAUGGUGCCACGCGCCGCAGAGCCCGGCUACCUGGUGACCAAGGUGGUGGCGGUGGACGCAGACUCAGGACACAACGCUUGGCUGUCCUACCACGUGCUGCAGGCCAGCGAGCCCGGGCUCUUCAGCCUGGGGUUGCGCACGGGUGAGGUGCGCACAGCGCGUGCCUUGGGCGACAGGGACGCGGCCCGCCAGCGCCUGCUGGUCGCUGUGCGUGAUGGAGGACAGCCGCCACUCUCCGCCACCGCCACGCUGCACCUAAUCUUCGCGGAUAGCCUGCAAGAGGUAUUGCCAGACCUCAGCGACCGCCCUGAGCCCUCUGACCCCCAGACGGAACUGCAGUUUUACCUGGUUGUGGCCUUGGCCUUGAUCUCAGUGCUCUUUCUCCUCGCGGUGAUUCUAGCGAUCGCCCUGCGCCUGCGACGUUCCUCCAGCCUCGACACUGAGGGCUGCUUUCAAACCGGUCUCUGCUCCAAGUCUGGGCCCGGGGUUCCUCCCAACCACAGCGAGGGGACUUUGCCCUAUUCCUACAAUCUAUGUAUUGCCUCUCAUUCUGCAAAGACAGAGUUUAAUUCUCUCAACCUGACACCGGAAAUGGCUCCCCCUCAGGAUCUGCUGUGUGAUGAUCCUUCUAUGGUUGUAUGUGCCAGUAAUGAAGAUCACAAAAUCGCUUAUGACCCUUCUUUGUCUUCGCACCAAGCCCCGCCCAACACGGACUGGCGUUUCUCUCAGGCCCAGAGACCCGGCACCAGCGGCUCCCAAAAUGGCGAUGACACCGGCACCUGGCCCAACAACCAGUUUGACACAGAGAUGCUGCAAGCCAUGAUCUUGGCGUCCGCCAGUGAAGCUGCUGAUGGGAGCUCCACCCUGGGAGGGGGUGCCGGCACCAUGGGAUUGAGCGCCCGCUACGGACCCCAGUUCACCCUGCAGCACGUGCCCGACUACCGCCAGAAUGUCUACAUCCCAGGCAGCAAUGCCACACUGACCAACGCAGCUGGCAAGCGGGAUGGCAAGGCCCCAGCAGGUGGCAAUGGCAACAAGAAGAAGUCGGGCAAGAAGGAGAAGAAGUAACAUGGAGGCCAGGCCAAGAGCCACAGGGCGGCCUCUCCCCAACCAGCCCAGCUUCUCCUUACCUGCACCCAGGCCUCAGAGUUUCAGGGCUAACCCCCAGAAUACUGGUAGGGGCCAAGGCCAUGCUCCCCUUGGGAAACAGAAACAAGUGCCCAGUCAGCACCUACCCCUUCCCCCCCAGGGGGUUGAAUAUGCAAAAGCAGUUCCGCUGGGAACCCCCAUCCAAUCAACUGCUGUACCCAUGGGGGUAGUGGGGUUACUGUAGACACCAAGAACCAUUUGCCACACCCCGUUUAGUUACAGCUGAACUCCUCCAUCUUCCAAAUCAAUCAGGCCCAUCCAUCCCAUGCCUCCCUCCUCCCCACCCCACUCCAACAGUUCCUCUUUCCCGAGUAAGGUGGUUGGGGUGUUGAAGUACCAAGUAACCUACAAGCCUCCUAGUUCUGAAAAGUUGGAAGGGCAUCAUGACCUCUUGGCCUCUCCUUUGAUUCUCAAUCUUCCCCCAAAGCAUGGUUUGGUGCCAGCCCCUUCACCUCCUUCCAGAGCCCAAGAUCAAUGCUCAAGUUUUGGAGGACAUGAUCACCAUCCCCAUGGUACUGAUGCUUGCUGGAUUUAGGGAGGGCAUUUUGCUACCAAGCCUCUUCCCAACGCCCUGGGGACCAGUCUUCUGUUUUGUUUUUCAUUGUUUGACGUUUCCACUGCAUGCCUUGACUUCCCCCACCUCCUCCUCAAACAAGAGACUCCACUGCAUGUUCCAAGACAGUAUGGGGUGGUAAGAUAAGGAAGGGAAGUGUGUGGAUGUGGAUGGUGGGGGCAUGGACAAAGCUUGACACAUCAAGUUAUCAAGGCCUUGGAGGAGGCUCUGUAUGUCCUCAGGGGACUGACAACAUCCUCCAGAUUCCAGCCAUAAACCAAUAACUAGGCUGGACCCUUCCCACUACAUAAUAGGGCUCAGCCCAGGCAGCCAGCUUUGGGCUGAGCUAACAGGACCAAUGGAUUAAACUGGCAUUUCAGUCCAAGGAAGCUCGAAGCAGGUUUAGGACCAGGUCCCCUUGAGAGGUCAGAGGGGCCUCUGUGGGUGCUGGGUACUCCAGAGGUGCCACUGGUGGAAGGGUCAGCGGAGCCCCAGCAGGAAGGGUGGGCCAGCCAGGCCAUUCUUAGUCCCUGGGUUGGGGAGGCAGGGAGCUAGGGCAGGGACCAAAUGAACAGAAAGUCUCAGCCCAGGAUGGGGCUUCUUCAACAGGGCCCCUGCCCUCCUGAAGCCUCAGUCCUUCACCUUGCCAGGUGCCGUUUCUCUUCCGUGAAGGCCACUGCCCAGGUCCCCAGUGCGCCCCCUAGUGGCCAUAGCCUGGUUAAAGUUCCCCAGUGCCUCCUUGUGCAUAGACCUUCUUCUCCCACCCCCUUCUGCCCCUGGGUCCCCGGCCAUCCAGCGGGGCUGCCAGAGAACCCCAGACCUGCCCUUACAGUAGUGUAGCGCCCCCUCCCUCUUUCGGCUGGUGUAGAAUAGCCAGUAGUGUAGUGCGGUGUGCUUUUACGUGAUGGCGGGUGGGCAGCGGGCGGCGGGCUCCGCGCAGCCGUCUGUCCUUGAUCUGCCCGCGGCGGCCCGUGUUGUGUUUUGUGCUGUGUCCACGCGCUAAGGCGACCCCCUCCCCCGUACUGACUUCUCCUAUAAGCGCUUCUCUUCGCAUAGUCACGUAGCUCCCACCCCACCCUCUUCCUGUGUCUCACGCAAGUUUUAUACUCUAAUAUUUAUAUGGCUUUUUUUCUUCGACAAAAAAAUAAUAAAACGUUUCUUCUGAAAA